UGCAUUUCCCACUUCUGACUCUGUGCCUGCUGUUCCCUGCUGGGAAGAAGGAAAGCCAGUGAUGCUGGCUUGAGGCUGUAGUGGGAGGCCCAGCGGAUUGUGAGAAGCCAGCCCGGGCAGUGAGUGUGGAUGGCUUGGCAGGUGAGCCUGCCAGAGCUGGAGGACCGGCUUCAGUGUCCCAUCUGCCUGGAGGUCUUCAAGGAGCCCCUGAUGCUGCAGUGUGGCCACUCUUACUGCAAGGGCUGCCUGGUUUCCCUGUCCUGCCACCUGGAUGCCGAGCUGCGCUGCCCCGUGUGCCGGCAGGCGGUGGACGGCAGCAGCUCCCUGCCCAACGUCUCCCUGGCCAGGGUGAUCGAAGCCCUGAGGCUCCCUGGGGACCCGGAGCCCAAGGUCUGCGUGCACCACCGGAACCCGCUCAGCCUUUUCUGCGAGAAGGACCAGGAGCUCAUCUGUGGCCUCUGCGGUCUGCUGGGCUCCCACCAACACCACCCGGUCACGCCCGUCUCCACCGUCUACAGCCGCAUGAAGGAGGAGCUCGCAGCCCUCAUCUCUGAGCUGAAGCAGGAGCAGAAAAAGGUGGAUGAGCUCAUCGCCAAACUGGUGAACAACCGGACCCGAAUCGUCAAUGAGUCGGAUGUCUUCAGCUGGGUGAUCCGCCGCGAGUUCCAGGAGCUGCACCACCUGGUGGAUGAGGAGAAGGCCCGCUGCCUGGAGGGGAUAGGGGGUCACACCCGUGGCCUGGUGGCCUCCCUGGACAUGCAGCUGGAGCAGGCCCAGGGAACCCGGGAGCGGCUGGCCCAAGCCGAGUGUGUGCUGGAACAGUUCGGCAAUGAGGACCACCACAAGUUCAUCCGGAAGUUCCACUCCAUGGCCUCCAGAGCAGAGAUGCCGCAGGCCCGGCCCUUAGAAGGCGCAUUCAGCCCCAUCUCCUUCAAGCCAGGCCUCCACCAGGCUGACAUCAAGCUGACCGUGUGGAAAAGGCUCUUCCGGAAAGUUUUGCCAGGGAGCAGCCCUGUACUGGCCCCUUCUAGACCCUGGGGCUAGAGAGAUGAGGAAGACACAGCCCCUCUCCUUGGGGAGUUCAGGGCCUCCAUCAGCUUCUGUGGGCCGGGUCUGCUGCCCUCCACGUGGCCUCACAGACCCUCUGUGAUCUCCCUCCCAGCCCCGGAGCCUCUCAAGUUGGACCCUGCCACUGCCCACCCACUCCUGGAGCUCUCCAAGGGCAACACGGUGGUGCAGUGCGGGCUUCUGGCCCAGCGGCGAGCCAGCCAGCCUGAGCGCUUCGACUACAGCACCUGCGUCCUGGCCAGCCGCGGCUUCUCCUGCGGCCGCCACUACUGGGAGGUGGUGGUGGGCAGCAAGAGCGACUGGCGCCUGGGGGUCAUCAAGGGCACAGCCAGCCGUAAGGGCAAGCUGAACAGGUCCCCCGAGCACGGCGUGUGGCUGAUCGGCCUGAAGGAGGGCCGGGUGUACGAAGCCUUUGCCUGCCCCCGGGUACCCCUGCCCGUGGCCGGCCACCCCCACCGCAUCGGGCUCUACCUGCACUAUGAGCAGGGCGAACUCACCUUCUUCGAUGCCGACCGCCCCGAUGACCUGCGGCCGCUCUACACCUUCCAGGCCGACUUCCAGGGCAAGCUCUACCCCAUCCUGGACACCUGCUGGCACGAGAGGGGCAGCAACUCGCUGCCCAUGGUGCUGCCCCCGCCCAGCGGGCCUGGCCCCCUCAGCCCCGAGCAGCCCACCAAGCUGUAGGGCCGCCCGGAGUCCUGCCGGCCCACAGGCCCAUCCCGGCGGGGCACCGGGGACUCGCGGGCUUCUGCUGGGUCCCGCCUGAGGUGAUAUCGUCACUGUUUAGGAAGGUCUUCAGGCCUGUGUGUCCCUGGAACAUGUAAUGAUAGGGAACAGGACCCCAGUCCCUUUCCCCUCAGCCAAGGGUGUAUUUGUAAACUUCGGCCCCCAGGCCUUGGCAGCCAGGGACACACUGAAAUCCCCAUGGUUCCUGCCACUUGCUAACCAUGCUAUCUGCGCAGACGCUUCCGAGGGCAGAAAUAGUCCCAUGUAUACCUUUUCCAUAUUACUGUGAACUUUCAACUACUAUCAAGGAUAAUAAAUUUGACAUUAUUUCUUUCUCUUUAAA